GGCGCGCGCCCCGCACGCGCGCCCCGCACGCGCAUAACGGCUUGGCUUACCUGUAACGGGUACACUUCGCUUCGCGUUCCUCGCUUGGCCUUGCGUUCCUAGCUUGGCUUGGCUGUUAGUAGCUUUGCCUGGUGUUUCUUGCUUGGAUUGGCGUUUCCUCCCUCGCAUUCCUUUGCUGGACUUGACCUUUUCUCUGCUGGGUUUGGCAUUCCCUUGACUGGGCUGGGUGUUUCCUUGGGAGGGGGGGCUUGGCCUUUCCUGGGGUGGGCGUGGGGUCCCCCUGGUGGGCGUGGGCUUUCCCCGGGUGGGUGUGGGUUUUCCCUGGGUGGGGUGGGCUGGGCUCCCUUGCUGGGCUUGGCAAGUUUUGGCUGGGAUUGACCUUUCUCUUCAAACAGAUUGGAAACCCAGGGUUUCCUGCUAGUUGGUGAAACUGGUUGGUAGACGCGAUCUGUUCGCUACUACCGGCCUCCCCUGGCUGUUAAAAGCAGAUGGUGGCUGAGGUUUGUUCAAUGCCCGCUGCCUCUGCUGUGAAGAAGCCAUUUGAUCUCAGGAGCAAGAUGGGCAAGUGGUGCCACCACCGCUUCCCCUGCUGCAGGGGGAGCGGCAAGAGCAACAUGGGCACUUCUGGAGACCACGACGACUCCUUUAUGAAGACGCUCAGGAGCAAGAUGGGCAAGUGUUGCCACCACUGCUUCCCCUGCUGCAGGGGGAGCGGCACGAGCAAUGUGGGCACUUCUGGAGACCAUGACAACUCCUUUAUGAAGACACUCAGGAGCAAGAUGGGCAAGUGGUGCUGUCACUGCUUCCCCUGCUGCAGGGGGAGCGGCAAGAGCAACGUGGGCACUUGGGGAGACUACGACGACAGCGCCUUCAUGGAGCCGAGGUACCACGUCCGUCGAGAAGAUCUGGACAAGCUCCACAGAGCUGCCUGGUGGGGUAAAGUCCCCAGAAAGGAUCUCAUCGUCAUGCUCAGGGACACUGACAUGAACAAGAGGGACAAGCAAAAGAGGACUGCUCUACAUUUGGCCUCUGCCAAUGGAAAUUCAGAAGUAGUACAACUCCUGCUGGACAGACGAUGUCAACUUAACGUCCUUGACAACAAAAAAAGGACAGCUCUGAUAAAGGCCGUACAAUGCCAGGAAGAUGAAUGUGUGUUAAUGUUGCUGGAACAUGGCGCUGAUGGAAAUAUUCAAGAUGAGUAUGGAAAUACCGCUCUACACUAUGCUAUCUACAAUGAAGAUAAAUUAAUGGCCAAAGCACUGCUCUUAUAUGGUGCUGAUAUUGAAUCAAAAAACAAGUGUGGCCUCACACCACUUUUGCUUGGCGUACAUGAACAAAAACAGCAAGUGGUGAAAUUUUUAAUCAAGAAAAAAGCUAAUUUAAAUGCACUUGAUAGAUAUGGAAGAACUGCCCUCAUACUUGCUGUAUGUUGUGGAUCAGCAAGUAUAGUCAAUCUUCUACUUGAGCAAAAUGUUGAUGUAUCUUCUCAAGAUCUAUCUGGACAGACGGCCAGAGAGUAUGCUGUUUCUAGUCAUCAUCAUGUAAUUUGUGAAUUACUUUCUGACUAUAAAGAAAAACAGAUGCUAAAAAUCUCUUCUGAAAACAGCAAUCCAGAACAAGACUUAAAGCUGACAUCAGAGGAAGAGUCACAAAGGCUUAAAGUCAGUGAAAAUAGCCAGCCAGAGAAAAUGUCUCAAGAACCAGAAAUAAAUAAGGACUGUGAUAGAGAGGUUGAAGAAGAAAUAAAGAAGCAUGGAAGUAAUCCUGUGGGAUUACCAGAAAACCUGACUAAUGGUGCCAGUGCUGGCAAUGGUGAUGAUGGAUUAAUUCCACAAAGGAAGAGCAGAAAACCUGAAAAUCAGCAAUUUCCUGACACUGAGAAUGAAGAGUAUCACAGUGACGAACAAAAUGAUACCCAGAAACAACUUUCUGAAGAACAGAACACUGGAAUAUCACAAGAUGAGAUUCUGACUAAUAAACAAAAGCAGAUAGAAGUGGCUGAAAAGGAAAUGAAUUCUGAGCUUUCUCUUAGUCAUAAGAAAGAAGAAGAUCUCUUGCGUGAAAACAGCAUGUUGCGGGAAGAAAUUGCCAAGCUAAGACUGGAACUAGAUGAAACAAAACAUCAGAACCAGCUAAGGGAAAAUAAAAUUUUGGAGGAAAUUGAAAGUGUAAAAGAAAAACUUCUAAAGACUAUACAACUGAAUGAAGAAGCAUUAACGAAAACCAGUAUUUAAGUACAGUGGACAGCUUAGGAUUUUGACAACUGAGAAUGCUCAGUUCUGAACUGGAGAAUGUAAGACACAACUAGGAAACACUGGAAAUGGAAAUUCAAUCAUGUCAUUGUAGACUGACUACUGCUCUACAUGAUUGUGAUCAAAGUCAGAUAGCUGAAAGGGACUUCUUUCCAGAGAACAAACAUCAACAGGUUUAUUUACAGGAGAAAAUGAAUUCUUAUAUAUCUCACCUAAAAGAUAACAGUGAGAUUCUUUCUGAACAACUCUAACGCUGACAGUAAAAUUAACAACCUAAAAAUUAAGCUCCAUCACACAGGAUAAAUUCUGAGAGAAAAGAUGAGGCAGGCCACCAUCUUUCCUGUUUGGGCAACUUAGUCAUUCCAGCGUGCGGGCUUUGGAGAGUACAAACUCACCAGGGACAGAAGAGAUCCUGUGGCAUAGCACAGCUGCUUUACCAAAUCAUGACCAGAAUGCUUCUGUAAGCAGGCCCCUGAUCCUGUUCCUCGUCACUGGACAGGAUCUCCCACCUGAGGCCUCCAGCUACACCCACCAGUGUUCCCUGGCCAAUGGAGAUUUGAAACCUUCCUGGGACAGAGUUCCCAGAGAGAGGGGUGGGCCAUGAUGGGCAGGUCUUCCUGGCCUGGGUCUCCAGCCAGCCCCCCACUUGAGCCUUCAAGCCAGUAGCAACUCAGCAACUCCCUGGACAGAGCUUCCAGGAGCAACAGAAAUCCUCUCUGCCACUGCCUCUGCAGUGGAACUGCCCUUGCUACCCUCAGAAUAUCAAGGGAGCAAAGACCCUAAGUGCCAUAUUGACACCUCCAACAAGCUGCAGUUGACACAAGGAACAAGUCAGUCCAUCUUCCACGGGUACAACACACCCCUUACUGCUCAUCACCAGACAAGGAACCCUGGCUUGGGCCCACAGCACAGACCCUCCAUCCUGGGGUGAUUACAUUAAGUAACUCCUAACUUACACCUCUCUGGGGUGGAGCCCCCAGAAGACAAGGAAAGUGGUGGAGCAGCAAGUCAGCUGAUGUGGAGCCCGGAGGGCAGGGACAUCUAUGUCUCUAGGCUCCACUUGCUCUUAUGAGACACUUUAUCCCAGCACUUAAGGAGUGCUGAGGUCAGACCAGCCCCAUCUCACGUGCAAGAUUGCCCAGCACAGAUCAGGUCUAAGAGUUCUCUUCCUAAAAAGGGGGACUUGCUUAAAAAAGAAGUCUGGCCGCGUUUGUGUAGAGCAGUUGUGCUGUGCUGAGGAUUCACUUUUGAGAGAGUUCUCCUCUGAGACCUGAUCUCUGCUGGGCAGUCUUGCACAUGAGAUGGGGCUGGUCUGACCUCAGCACCCCUUAGUCUGCUUGCCUCUCCCAGGACCCCAGCCAGGCCACACCUGCUUAGAGGGCACUUCUGGGUGCCCACACCAUAGCUUCUGUACAAGCGGACCGUGGCUGAUCAGUGGAGAGCUGCAGCAAGGUGACCUCUACAGCCACGUACCAGCCUGCACAUUACCUCUCCAUACUGCAGCCCUUUAUAUGGAAACUUUCUACAUCACUUAGCUGUGUGUGUUUACACAGGUGGGUUUUGUUGUACUUGCCCUAACAGCAUAUGGGAAUGCAGCACACACCCCAACCCACACCAACUGCCACUGAAGAUGAAGCCAUGGUGGGCACAGAACCAAAAACCCCACCCCUGCUAGCAUCUCACCCUUGAGGUAAUGCUGUGCAGAGGAAAAGGGACCUUCUUAUACCCUGAGUGACCACUGUUGCUUGGGGGGGAUCAGAGAAGGCACCUUCACUGGCCAGCCACCCACCCCAAACCAGAACUACCUCCAGUGCAACAGCACACACAGUCAGCAGGGGCCCCCUGGCCCACACCCCAGCUGUUUUGCCUCCACCACUAGGUGAAUGCCCACAGGGAGGCAGGGACUUUUGCAUCUGCUAGCAUUCUGCCACAGCUGCCGCACUUUGGUCCCCUCAGUGCGGUGGACUCCAAACCUCGAGGAGCCAGAGAACAAAGUUGUGGCCCAAUACAAGUUCCCCAGAGUUAAAGCACACAGUCCAAGCAUUGGGAGCUGCAUGUUGGCCCCUUAAAAUCCUCCAAACACAAAACCUGUUGGCUGAAUCCACCUUACACCACAAUCAAAUCCUCAAGGUCAUCAGAUAUAAUAAAGGAAAAAUACCCUGUCCAAAGGUCAGCAGCCUCAAAGAUUGAAGGUGGAUAAGCCCAUAAAGAUGAGAAAAAGACUGUGCAAGAACACUGAAAACUCAAAAAUUCAGCAUGCUUUCUUUUCUCCAAAUGACUGCAUCAACUCUCCAGCAAGUGUUCAGAACUGGGCUGAGGCUGAGAUGUCUGAAAUGAUACAAGCAGAGUUCAGGAUAUGGGUAGGAACAAAGUUCCCUGAGUGAAAGAGGUAUGUUGUAAUCCAAUACAAGGAAGCUAAAAAUCAUUGUAAAACAUUGCAGGAACUAACAGACAAAAUAGCAAGUAUAAAGAAGAAAAUAACUGACCUGACAGAGCUGUAAAUCACACUAGAAGAAUUUUCAUAAUGCAGUCACACGGUGAUUGUGUGUGAUUGCAUUAUGAAAAUUAUUGUAGUAUGUGUGGGCACCUGAGAGUGCCCUGUAAGCAGAUGUGGCCAGGCUGGGGUCCUGGGAGAGGCAAGCAGACUAGGGAGGGCUGAGGUCAGACCAGCUCCAUCUCAUGUGCAAGACCAUCCAACAGAAUAGACCAAGAAGAGGAAAGAAUCCCAGAACCUGGAAACUGGCUUUCUGAAAUAAAACAGGCAAACAAGAAUGGGGGAAAAAAGAAUGAAAGGGAAUGAACAAAACAUCCGAGAAAUAUGGGAUUAUAUAAACGACUAAAUCUAUGACUGAUUAAUGUACCUGAAAGAGAUGAGGAGAAUGGAACCAACUUGGAAAACACAUUUCAGAAUAUCAUUCAUGAGAAUGUCCCCAACCUAGCCAGACAGGCCAACACUCAACUUCAGGAAAUCCAGAGAACCUCAGUAAGAUAUGCCAUGAGAAGAUCAUCCCCAAGACACAUAAUCAUCAGAUUCUCUGCGGUCAAAAUGAAAGAAAAAGUGUUAAAGGCAGCUAGGGAGAAAGGCAACAUCACCUGCAAAGGAAAUUCCAUCAGACUUAGCAGACCUCUCAACUGAAACUGUACAAGCCAGAAAAGAUAUUCAACAUCUUAAAGAAAAGAAAUUUCAACCCAGAAUUUCAUGUCCAGCAAAAUUAAGCAUCAUAAGUGAAGGAGAAACAAGAUCCUUUUCAGACAAGCAAAUGCUGAGGGAAUUCAUUAUCACCAGACCUACCUUACAAGAGCUCCUGAAGGAAGCACUAAAUAUGGAAAGAAAAGACCACCACCAGCCACUACAAAAACACACUGAAGUACACAGACAAGUGAUGCUAAAAACCAACCACAUACAUAAGUCUGCAAAAAAGCCAGCUGACAGCAUGACGAGAGGAUCAAAUCCACACAUACCAUUACUAACCUUAAAUGGAAAUGGGCUAAAUGCUCCAAUUGAAAGACACAGGGGGCAAGCUGGAUAAAGAACCAAGACCCAUUGGAGUAUGCCGUCUUCAAGAAACCCAUCUCACAUGCAGUGCCCUACAUAGGCUCAAAAUAAAGGAAUGGAGAAAAAUAUUUCAAGGAAAUGGAAAAUAGAAAAAAGCAGGUGUUGCACUCCUAGUUUCUGACAAAGCAGACUAUACCAAUAAAGAUUAAAAAGAAAAAAAAAAAGACAGAGGGCUGGGCGCGGUGGUUCACGCCUGUAAUCCCAGCACUUUCGGAGGCUGAGACAGAUGGAUCACAAGGUCAGGAGAUCGAGACCAUCCUGGCUAACACGGUGAAACCCCGUCUCUACGAAAAAUACAAAAAAUUAGCUGGGCAUGGUGGCGGGUGCCUGUAGUCCCAGCUACUUGGGAGGCUGAGGCAGGAGAAUGGUGUGAACCUGGGAAGUGGAGCUUGCAGUGAGCCAAGAUCGUGCCACUGCACUGCAGCCCAGGCGAGACAGUGAGACUCCGUCUCAAAAAAAAAAAAAAAAAAAAAAAAAAAAAGAGAGAAGGAGAUUACAAAGGUGGUCCUGACCUUUGAUAAAUCUCAUUAUUGCUUGAUACCAACCUGGGCUAUCUUUAUUGCCCAAACCAAUAGGAUAAUGUGCUGAGGUUAGGGAGCUUCUCCCCUGCAGAGAAUCCCUGAUCUCCCAAAAUUUGGUUGAGAUCUAAGGUUGAUUUUGCUAUACAACUCCUUUUCUGAAGUUUUACUUAUUUCCAACAAGGCAAGUUUUCCUGCUUCCGUGAUGAUGGAGAGCAGGCACCUCCUUUCUUGAGUUUCAGCUUGCUUCUGACAGGGAAGGUGAGUGUAAGUUUUUUCCAGCUUCUAAGAUGGCAGAGAACAAUCACCAGCCUGAGACUUAUUUCCAGCAGAGCUGGAAGCUGUAUCUUCAAAAUAUGUCUGUUUGACUCAAAACAAUCAAGGUAUUCAACAGGAGUUAUUAUGUAUGAAAAAAUACAACAGGAAUGUAAAAAUCUUGAGGAGGCUAAAAAGAUGUUGGAAAAAGUAAUAUUAAAUCUUAAAAAACGUAUGGAAAGUACACAUUGGUGAAGACACAUUGGUGAAGUACAAAAAUAUAAAUUGGAUCUAGAAGAAAGGGCAAUGCAGGCAAUGGAAAAAUUAGUACAAAUCCCUUUACAGUAAUGAUUCUCAGUGUGGAGUCAUUUGAUUAUUAAGACCCAUUGACAUGAGAUUACAUCCUCUGCCUAUAAAAAUCCUGGAAGAAAACCUAGGAAAUAUUCACCUGGACAUUGCACUUGGCAAUGAAUUUAUGGAUAGAAAAUGCAGUUGAAAGAUAUUUCAUAAAGGAAGAAAAAGUAAGAAUACAGCUUUAACCGUUUAUUGUGGUGGAGUCUUUAAGAUUUUCUCUACCUUGAGUGCGCCAGGCGCGGGGAGCCUAGGACCUGGAGCGAGAGCCGCCUACCUGCAGCCGCCGCCCACGGCACGGCAGCCACCAUGGCGCUCCUGCUGCGCUUCGUGCUCCUGUGCAGAGCCGCGGAUUUCAUCAGAGGUUGGAGUAUCACUACUCCUGAGCAGAUGAUUGAAAAAGCCAAAGGGGAAACUGCCUAUCUGCCAUGCAAAUUUACGCUUAGUCCUGAAGACCAGGGACCACUGGACAUCGAGUGGCUGAUAUCACCAGCUGAUAAUCAGAAGGUGGAUCAAGUGAUUAUUUUAUAUUCUGGAGACAAAAUUUAUGAUGACUACUAUCCAGAUCUGAAAGGCCGAGUACAUUUUAAGAGUAAUGAUCUCAAAUCUGGUGAUGCAUCAAUAAAUGUAACGAAUUUUCAGCUGUCAGAUAUUGGCACAGAUCAGUGCAAAGUGAAAAGAGCUCCUGGUGUUGCAAAUAGGAAGAUUCAGCUGGUAGUUCUUGGUAAGCCUUCAGGUACAAGAUGUUACGUUGAUGGAUCAGAAGAAAUUGAAAGUGACUUUAAAUUAAAAUGUGAACCAAAAGAAGGUUCACUUCCAUUACAGUAUGAGUGGCAAAAAUUGUCUGACUCACAGAAAAUGCCCACUUCAUGGUUAGCAGAAAUGACUUCAUCUGUUAUAUCUGUAAAAAUGUUUCUUCUGAGUACUCUGGGACAUACAGCUGUACAUCAGAAACAGAGUGGGCUCUGAUCAGUGCCUGUUGCGUGUAAACGUUGUCCCUCCUUCAAAUAAAGCUGGACUAAUUGCAGGAGCCAUUAUAGGAACUUUGCUUGCUCUAGUGCUCAUUGGUCUUAUCAUCUUUUGCUGUCGUAAAAAGCGCAGAGAAGAAAAAUAUGAAAAGGAAGUUCAUCACGAUAUCAAGGAAGAUGUGCCGCCUCCAAAGAGCCGCACGUCCACUGCCAGAAGCUACAUAGGCAGUAAUCAUUCAUCCCUGGGAUCCAUAUCUCCUUCCAACAUGGAAGGAUAUUCCAAGACUCAGUAUAAACAAGUACCAAGUGAAGACUUUGAACGCACUCCUCAGAGUCCGACUCUCCCACCUGCUAAGGUAGCUGCCCCUAAUCUAAGUCCAAUGGGCGCGAUUCCUGUGAUGAUUCCCGCACAGAGCAAGGAUGGGUCUAUAGUAUAGAGCCUCCAUACGUCUCAUCUGUGCUCUCCGUGUUCCUUUCCUUUUUUUGAUAUAUGAAAACCUAUUCUGGUCUAAAUUUUGUUACUAGCCUCAGAAUGUAUCAAAAAAUAAGUUAAUCAGGAGCUGUAAGGAAUAUAUUUUUAAAAAUUUUUGUUUGGUUAUAUCGAAAUAGUUACGGGCAUUAAAGUUAGUAAAGACAAGUUUA